AGUGAAUGCGUAGUCCCAGCCUCAGCACAGGGGAGCCACCUUGAAGCUCUCAAAUAUCACUGUUGUGAAUACAGAGAGGGAAAACCAACUGUAACGUGCCACCCAAAUGUAAGUUUUACUCAUAUUUUGAUGUUAGGAUGGAUAGCUUGGAAAAAGUUGGAGGGUACGGCCUUUACUAUGAGGCAUCUAUGAAGGAUCAGGAAUGGAUGUAGACAAGGAACUAGGAAUGGAAAGUGUUAAAGCUGGAGCCUCUGGAAAACCAGAAAUGAGGCUGGGCACUCAGGAAGAAACAAGUGAAGGUGAUGCUAAUGAAAGCUCAUUACUAGUCCUGUCCAGCAACGUGCCUCUCCUGGCCCUAGAGUUCUUGGAAAUAGCCCAGGCCAAAGAGAAGGCCUUUCUCCCCAUGGUCAGCCACACGUUCCACAUGCGCACAGAGGAGUCUGAUGCCUCACAGGAGGGCGAUGACCUACCCAAGUCCUCAGCAAACACCAGCCAUCCCAAGCAGGAUGACAGCCCCAAGUCCUCAGAAGAAACCAUCCAGCCCAAGGAGGGUGACAUCCCCAAGGCCCCAGAAGAAACCAUCCAAUCCAAGAAGGAGGACCUCCCCAAGUCCUCAGAAAAAGCCAUCCAGCCCAAAGAGAGUAACAUCCCCAAGUCCUCAGCAAAACCCAUCCAGCCCAAGCUGGGCAAUAUUCCCAAGGCCUCAGUGAAGCCCAGCCAGCCCAAGGAGGGUGACAUCCCCAAGGCCCCAGAAGAAACCAUCCAAUCCAAGAAGGAGGACCUCCCCAAGUCCUCAGAAGAAGCCAUCCAGCCCAAAGAGGGUGACAUCCCCAAGUCCUCAGCAAAACCCAUCCAGCCCAAGCUGGGCAAUAUUGCCAAGACCUCAGUGAAGCCCAGCCAGCCCAAGGAGAGUGAUAUCCCCAAGUCCCCAGAAGAAACCAUCCAGCCCAAGGAGGGUGACAUCCCCAAGUCCUCAGCAAAGCCCAUCCAGCCCAAGCUGGGCAAUAUUCCCAAGGCCUCAGUGAAGCCCAGCCAGCCCAAGGAGGGUGACAUCUCCAAGUCCCCAGAAGAAGCCAUCCAGCCCAAGGAGGGUGACCUCCCCAAGUCCCUAGAGGAAGCCAUCCAGCCCAAGGAGGGUGACAUCCCCAAGUCCCCAGAAGAAGCCAUCCAGCCCAAGGAGGGUGACAUCCCCAAGUCCCUAGAGGAAGCCAUCCAGCCUAAGGAGGGUGACAUCCCCAAGUCCCCAGAAGAAACCAUCCAGCCCAAGAAGGGUGACAUCCCCAAGUCCCCAGAAGAAGCCAUCCAGCCCAAGGAGGGUGACAUUCCCAAGUCUCCAAAACAAGCCAUCCAGCCCAAGGAGGGUGACAUUCCCAAGUCCCUAGAGGAAGCCAUCCCACCCAAGGAGAUUGACAUCCCCAAGUCCCCAGAAGAAACCAUCCAGCCCAAGGAGGAUGACAGCCCCAAGUCCCUAGAAGAAGCCACCCCAUCCAAGGAGGGUGACAUCCUAAAGCCUGAAGAAGAAACAAUGGAGUUCCCGGAGGGGGACAAGGUGAAAGUGAUCCUGAGCAAGGAGGACUUUGAGGCAUCACUGAAGGAGGCCGGGGAGAGGCUGGUGGCUGUGGACUUCUCGGCCACGUGGUGUGGGCCCUGCAGGACCAUCAGACCAUUCUUCCAUGCCCUGUCUGUGAAGCAUGAGGAUGUGGUGUUCCUGGAGGUGGACGCUGACAACUGUGAGGAGGUGGUGAGAGAGUGCGCCAUCAUGUGUGUCCCAACCUUUCAGUUUUAUAAAAAAGAAGAAAAGGUGGAUGAACUUUGCGGCGCCCUUAAGGAAAAACUUGAAGCAGUCAUUGCAGAAUUAAAGUAAACAUGUAUUCUGAAAACAUUGCAGACAGUCAGGUGUUUAUAGCUUUUGAGUUCUCUUUUAUUAUUUACACAAAGUGAUCAGGUAUAACAAAAGUGUAUGUCCAAAUGGCACUGCUUGUACAUGAUAAUAUUAACUCUACCCUUUUCAAAAAACAGUCCAAGCAUUAAAGUACAUUGCGACUGUGUUUCUGUUAGUGGGAGAGUAUAAAAUUAGAAAUUCCCAUGGUGAAGACUGCUAAGUCCCAUGGUUUCCUAUUUUUCAAUCUUGAUAUGUAUUUAUUUUUCACUUGUCUUUGAAAAUUUCACGCAUUUAGUGUUUGCAGCAAGACUGAAAAUUUAGAUAAUUUUUCUAUAGAGGUAGAUGACUGAAAGGUGAAUGGAAACUUCUUUUCUCAUGUCACACAUCUUUGGGGAUUCUGAUAAGAUAUGUUUGGAAAUAAGGAAUUUGAAAGAUUCACAUCUUAGCUAACCUCCUUCUUGUGCCGGAAGUGCUACGGAGGCCUUGGGAAAUUCAGUGGGUUUUCCAAGAUCUGAUUUGUUGGUGACGGAAAUGAGAUCAAGGCCGCUUCCAGAUUUCAAGUCCAGGGCUCUACCUACUAUAAUCUACGCUCACAAAAUCUCAGACAAGAGGUCGGAACUUCAGGUUUCUCGGAGGUUGAAGUCCUCUGGAUCUUUGCUGCCUUUAUGACAUCAGUGCCCUGAUGGCAGAGUUCCUGGUUCGUCUCCCUGGUAAUUGAGUUCAUAAUACCUAGACCUUCCUCUGACUUUUUUACUUAAAUUUGUUCUUAUUUUCAAUAUUGAACAAGCCAGCCUUUAACAUGACUCUACCAGCUUAGACAUAUAGGCCUAGACUUUAAUGAAUUAACCUAAUCACAGUGCUACCAGAGUCUUGUUUGGACAACUUAGUGAGCCCCAGAUGUCUAUGAGCCCAAAGUCCCAGGUCUGAACCAUAGACAGAGGCUUAGUCCAGAGUGGGUUUUUAAAAAUGAAUAAAACCAGCUUCAUUAGGUAUAAUUGAUAUACAAAGAACAGCACAUAUUUAAUGGAGGGAGUUGGAUGAGUUUGGAUGUGUUGCAUAUGCCCUUGAUUGCCAUCUCCACCAUCAAAGUAAUUAACACCUUCAUUGCCUCCAGAA